AUCUGCCCACCAUGGCCCUGGUGCUGAUCCUCCAGCUGCUGACCCUCUGGCCUCUGUGUCACACAGACAUCACUCCGUCUGUGGCCAUUAUAGUCCCCCCAGCUUCAUACCACCCUAAGCCAUGGCUGGGAGCUCAGCCGGCUACAGUUGUGACCCCUGGGGUCAACGUGACCUUGAGAUGCCGGGCACCCCAACCCGCUUGGAGAUUUGGACUUUUCAAGCCUGGAGAGAUCGCUCCCCUUCUCUUCCGGGAUGUGUCCUCCGAGCUGGCAGAAUUCUUUCUGGAGGAGGUGACUCCAGCCCAAGGGGGAAGUUACCGCUGCUGCUACCGAAGGCCAGACUGGGGGCCGGGUGUCUGGUCCCAGCCCAGCGAUGUCCUGGAGCUGCUGGUGACAGAGGAGCUGCCGCGGCCGUCGCUGGUGGCGCUGCCCGGGCCGGUGGUGGGUCCUGGCGCCAACGUGAGCCUGCGCUGCGCGGGCCGCCUGCGGAACAUGAGCUUCGUGCUGUACCGCGAGGGCGUGGCGGCCCCGCUGCAGUACCGCCACUCCGCGCAGCCCUGGGCCGACUUCACGCUGCUGGGCGCCCGCGCCCCCGGCACCUACAGCUGCUACUAUCACACGCCCUCCGCGCCCUACGUGCUGUCGCAGCGCAGCGAGGUGCUGGUCAUCAGCUGGGAAGGUGAGGGCCCUGAGGCCCGGCCCGCCUCCUCCGCCCCAGGAAUGCAGGCCCCAGGACCUCCGCCCUCAGACCCAGGAGCCCAGGCCCCCAGCCUCUCCUCCUUCAGACCCAGGGGUCUAGUCCUGCAGCCCCUCCUCCCUCAGACCCAGGAUUCCUGGGACCCAGCCCCUCCUCCCUCAGAUCCAGGAGUCUAGUCCUCCAGCUCCUCCUCCCUCAGACCCAGGAUUCCCGGGCCCCAGUACCUCCUCCCUCAGACCCAGGACUCCAGGCCCCCAGCCCCUCCUUCCUGGACCCAGGACUCCAGGCCCCCAGCCCCUCCUUCCUGAUCCAGCAGUCCAGGCCCCAGCCCCUUCUUCCUGGACCCAGGAGUUGAAGCCUCCAUCGACUCCCCCUCAACUUUGAGACUGUAGAGUCAGGUCCCUAAGUCCACCCCAGGGGCUGGAAACCUGGAGUUCAGGGCCCAGACUUUGGGGUCCGGGAGCUGAUGGCCCCUCUCUCCCGGCUCCGCCCGCAGACUCUGGCUCCUCCGACUACACCCGGGGGAACCUAGUCCGCCUGGGGCUGGCCGGGCUGGUCCUCAUCUCCCUGGGCGCGCUGGUCACUUUUGACUGGCGCAGUCAGAACCGCGCUCCUGCUGGUAUCCGCCCCUGAGCCCCAGGAGCACUGCAGCCCGAGACUUCCAACCUGAGUGGCGGAGAAGCUGGGACCCUGGGCUGGACUGUCCUUUCCUGCAGCCCCACAGUCCUGCUGGCUGAGCUCCGCGGAACGGUCCUUAGACCCCGCUGUGCCCUGUGCUGUAGCUUCUUUCCAGGCCUUUCCCAAGGAGUAGCUGAAAGGAAGACGCGAUUAGUGGUUAAGACUUCCAAGCCAGAAGACAGAGGGUUCGAAUCCCAGCACUGCCGUCUACUCACUGUAGUAGUAGCAGCUACAGAAAGGUAGUAGUGAGACGUGAAGCCAGCUGGACUUCCUGGGUUGAAUGGGGACCUGGAGAACUUUUCUGUCUUACAAGAGGAUUGUAAAAUGGACCAAUCAGCACUCUGUAAGAUGGACCAAUCAGCGCUCUGUAAAAUGGACCAAUCAGCAGGACACGGGCGGGGACAAUAAGGGAAUAAAAGCUGGCGAGCGCGGCACCCCACCAGAGUCUGCUUCCACGUUGUGGGAGCUUUGUUCUCUUGCUCUACACAAUAAAUCUUGCUGCUGCUAA